AUCAAAGGUGACAGCUUCCGGCAACUGAUGCCUCCACUGGCCACUCCUCCCUCCGUCCACCUGUCACUUCGGGUAGCUGGGAGGCCAGGUGAGGGGCGCGCACGGGGGAGGGGCGUGCAUAGUUGAGACAGAAACCCGGAAGACCCAACUGUGGCGCGGCACUGCUUGACCGAGGGGCUCCGGAGCCCAGCUGCACCGGCUGCGGUUUGAGCGCCCAGGGCCGGGGUGCGGGGUGGACCGCGGCGGCCCUUCGACCAAAGGUGCUUGAAGCUCGAGCCCAUUACUUUCUGUGGACUCUGACUCGAGCUGCAAAAGCUUUUCUGCACUGUUUUUCUCAUCUAUGUUAUGAAGAUAAUAAUUCCGGCCCUAACCGUAGUAUGCUUGCGAGAAUCCAACAAUAUGAUGUUUCUGAAAGCGCCGGCUGAACUAAGAGCGCGUGAAAUAGAAUGACAGACAGCUCUGCAAGAACGGAGGCCCUGUCUAUUUUGUACCCAGCUGUACGGUACUGGCGCCGAAAGACGUUCAAUAAAUACUUAUUGAAUGACGAAUACGCGUUAGGAGUUGGUAAAAUCUCUCAAGGCUUCACCUCCUCAGUGGGCUAGGUGCAAUUCUAACCAGGGGGCAAGUUUCCUUAGCUUUCCCUACGACCCCAGUUAGGCAGCUCAGGUUACUAUUGCAGCUUGAUGGCCCUUGGGACUCCAGGUUUUUGAGUGGACGUGGCUGCUACUGCAGCAGGUGAUCCACCAACCAAGUUCUCUAUCAGGGUAAUGUUAAGAAUAAACCUUGGCCGGGCGCGGUAGCUCACGCCUGUAAUCCCAGCACUUUGGGAGGCCAAGGUGGGUGGAUCACCUGAGGUCAGGAGUUCAAGACCAGCCUGGCCAACAUGGUGAAACCCCGUCUCUACUAAAAACACGAAAAAUUAGCCGGGUGUGGUGGCACGCGCCUGUAAUCCCAGCUACUCGGGAGGUUGAGGCAGGAGAAUCACUUGAACGCGGGAGGCGGAGGUUGCAGUGAGCCAAGACUGCUCCAUUGCACUCCAGCCCGGGCAACAAGAGUUAAACUCCAUCAAAAAAAAAAAACAAAAAACGAAUAAGCCUUUAUGAGAAAUUUUCUCUCCUACCAAAUAAUAACAAUAACAGCUUUCAUUUAAAAAAAAUGGAACCUUUUUCCUGUGACACUUUCGUGGCAUUACCUCCAGCAACAGUCGAUAACAGGAUUAUUUUUGGAAAAAAUUCAGAUAGACUCUAUGAUGAAGUACAAGAGGUGGUUUAUUUUCCUGCUGUAGUUCAUGAUAACCUGGGAGAACGUCUUAAGUGUACAUAUAUAGAAAUUGAUCAAGUUCCUGAAACAUAUGCUGUUGUCCUGAGUCGCCCAGCGUGGUUGUGGGGGGCAGAAAUGGGAGCCAAUGAGCAUGGAGUUUGCAUUGGGAAUGAAGCUGUAUGGGGAAGAGAAGAAGUUUGUGAUGAAGAAGCACUAUUAGGAAUGGACCUUGUCAGACUUGGCCUUGAAAGAGCUGAUACAGCUGAAAAAGCCCUCAAUGUCAUUGUUGACUUACUAGAAAAAUAUGGCCAGGGUGGAAAUUGCACAGAGGGUAGAAUGGUAUUUAGCUAUCACAACAGUUUCCUGAUAGCUGAUAGGAAUGAAGCCUGGAUUCUGGAGACUGCAGGGAAGUACUGGGCAGCAGAAAAAGUACAAGAGGGAGUUCGUAAUAUUUCUAAUCAACUUUCCAUAACAACCAAGAUUGCCCGGGAACACCCAGACAUGAGAAACUAUGCUAAGCGGAAAGGUUGGUGGGAUGGUAAAAAGGAGUUUGAUUUUGCUGCAGCAUAUUCCUAUCUUGACACAGCCAAGAUGAUGACUUCAUCAGGCAGAUACUGUGAGGGCUACAAGCUUCUAAAUAAGCACAAAGGAAAUAUAACUUUUGAAACAAUGAUGGAAAUUCUUCGAGAUAAACCAAGUGGCAUUAAUAUGGAGGGAGAAUUCCUGACCACUGCAAGCAUGGUUUCUAUUUUACCUCAAGACUCCAGCCUUCCUUGCAUUCACUUCUUUACAGGGACUCCUGAUCCUGAGAGAUCUGUUUUUAAGCCUUUCAUAUUUGUGCCACAUAUUUCACAACUAUUGGAUACCAGUUCACCAACAUUUGAACUUGAAGAUCUAGUUAAAAAGAAAUCACAUUUUAAGCCUGACAGAAGACACCCACUCUACCAAAAACAUCAACAGGCAUUGGAAGUAGUAAAUAAUAAUGAGGAAAAAGCCAAAAUAAUGUUGGACAACAUGAGGAAACUGGAGAAAGAACUAUUCAGAGAGAUGGAAUCAAUCCUUCAAAACAAGCAUCUUGAUGUGGAGAAAAUUGUUAAUCUCUUUCCUCAGUGUACAAAAGAUGAAAUUCAAAUUUAUCAGUCAAAUUUAUCAGUCAAAGUUAGUUCUUAGUGAUCAUAUGGUCAGCUAAUAUUAGUUCUUAGUGAUCAGUGGUCAGUAAUCUUCAAAGUCAGAAUCUAUCACCUUGGUAAAUUAUAUAAACCUAACUUGAGCAGAUCUGAUUAUUCUUGGAUAGUAUUCAAGUGGUAUCUUGACUAUUAAACUACGUAUAGUGUUGCUGAAAUAGAAAGAAAACAGCAUUGGAAUUGGAUUCAUGUAUCGUGGGAUACAGGUGUUAUUUCAGGUGAUGUACUUGCAUUAUUUUCUUUAGCCAUAGUAACUUUUUGUCACAAUAACUAAGUAUUCAAUUAUAUAUAAAGAGUGAAACAUUAAAAUGACGCAUGGAUUUAUAUUUAUUAUAAUUAUGUAGUACCCUCAAAUCAUUUUGUCAGUUACAUCAAGAAAGCAGAUUUUUCUUUAGUCAUGAAAAAUAUCUCAAGUGGUAAGUUGUUUGUGCUUUAGGCAAACAUUAACCAGCUCUAACAAGAAAAAUGUCUAGAUUUACACAUUGUCAAUACAGUAUAUUAGUUCUGCAAAUGCACUUUUGUUAAACUCAAACAUGCUCUUUGUCAAGACUUGGCUAACCAGUGAGCUUGUAGCUCUGAUUAUCUAGCAUUUUUAGGGUCAUUCUCCUUAAUAGGCUUUUAUGUUAAUAAGAUAUAUUUUUAGAAGAGCUUGUUUGGGAGAUUAGAGAAUAAGAUAAAAGAACCAAAACCUUAGGAUAUACUGUUUCUGGGUCUGAAAUCUCUCUCAUUGUUUACUUCUGUUCACUCAGUGAAAACAGAAACAAGAAUGAGGUAGUGGCAAUGAAAUAGAAUUAUUAGUAUAUUAUGAACAUUAUAACAUUUUGAACACUAUAAUGCAUUAUAUAUUAUGAACUUUUAUGAACUUUAUACAUGAGUAAUAGCUUCCUAAAGUUUAUAAAACAUUGUUUAGGUUACAUAAAGAUUACCAAGUAAGACUCAAAAUUGCAAAUAUAAACAAAAGAAAAAUCCAACUGAAAAUAACACUAAGUAUUUUUGAGUUCCUAGAAUGUCCAUUUUGGUAUUUGGUUACAUUAUCAUAUUUACUAGUCACUAUCAGCACAAUUAGGUUAAUAAAGAAGUGGGUCAUUAUAUUCAAAGAGUGCUCAGGAAGUUAUGUGUUCAAAGUUCUCUCAUAAAUACCAUCGUCUGCCUGAUACUGCUCUUGUCUAAUAGAGGGUUGACAUUACAAAAGAAAAGAUGUCUGACUCAAGAACUCAGUUGAUUCUGUUUGCCUUAAGUUUGGUUCAGUGAUAGGCUGUCUUCUAACCCCUAUACUCCUCUUCUCUCCUUUAAUAGAUGAGGAAACUAAGGGCAAACAGUUCGUUACACUUACGGGAAUCUUAUUUCCCUCUCUAGGGGCAGCAUGUUUUCACCUUCUCCUUUGCUGCCACCUUGGCCUAAACUAGCACCGUCUUUUAGCUAGACCAUUGCGUUAACUGUUCUCCUACACCCAUUUUUGUUCUUUAUUUCCACCCACAUGAGUCACUGCAGCCAAUCUAUUACAAAUUUAAAUCUGAUUAUGAAUUCCCCUCCUAAAACUCUUUUUUAAAAGAGACUUUAUUUUUUGGAGCAGUUUUAGGUUCACAGCAAAAUUGAACAGAAAGUACAGAGUUCCAAUACAGCCCCUAUCAGCAUACAUGCAUAGCCUCCCCCACUAUCAACAUCCCAGCACCAGAAUGGUACAUUUGUUAGAAUCAAUGGCCCUACAUUGACACAUUAUCACCCAAAGGCCAUGGUUCAAGUUAGAGAUCACUCUUGAUGUAGUACAUCCUAUGGGCUUUGAUAAUUAUAAAAUGACAUGUAUCCACCAUUAUAGUAUUAUACAGAGUAGUUUCACUGCCCUAAAAAUCUUCUGUGUUCUGCCUAUUUAUCCCACCCUCCCUCCAACCCCUGGCAACCACUGAUCUUUUUACUGUCUCCAUAGUUUUGCCUUUUCCAUAUGUCAUAUCAUUGGAAUCAUACAGUAUGUGACCUCUUAAGAUUGUCUUCUUUAACUUACUUAGUAAUAUCCAUUUAAGGUUCCUGCAUGUCUUUUCAUGACUUGAUAGCUCAUUUCUUUUAGUGCUAAGUAAUAUUCGAUUGUCUGAAUAUACUACUACUGAAGGACAUCUUGGUUGCUUCCAAGUUUUGAAAAUUAUGAAUAAACCUGCCGUAGACAUCCA